AAGAGAAACCCGAGUUUGAGGACCUUAUUUUAUUCUACGCUGUUUAGAUUUGUAUCCUCUGGUAAUUUAGUGGCAUUAGUCACCUGCUAAUUAAUCUUUUUCCUUUCCCCUGUGUUCCAUAUAGAGAAAAGUGGUAAAGAAUCUACCUCACUGGGAAUGUCAUCAUUACCAACUUCAGAUGGGUUUAACCAUCCCGCCCGUUCUUCAGGACAGAGUCCUGAUGUUGGUAAUCCUAUGAGUCUUGCUCGCUCUGUCUCUGCUUCAGUCUGCCCUAUCAAGCCCAGUGACUCAGAUCGCAUUGAACCUAAAGCUGUGAAGGCUUUGAAGGCUUCAGCUGAAUUCCAGCUAAACUCUGAAAAGAAAGAACAUCUUUCUUUACAAGAUCUUUCUGAUCAUGCUUCCUCAGCAGACCAUGCUCCAACAGACCAGAGUCCAGCUAUGCCUAUGCAGAAUUCAUCCGAAGAAAUAACUGUUGCAGGUAAUCUGGAGAAAUCUGCUGAAAGAAGCACCCAGGGCCUCAAAUUUCAUCUCCAUACAAGACAGGAAGCUAGUUUAUCUGUCACAUCUACUAGGAUGCAUGAACCACAGAUGUUUCUAGGUGAAAAGGAUUGGCAUCCAGAAAAUCAGAACCUGAGUCAAGUGAGUGACCCUCAGCAGCACGAAGAACCAGGGAAUGAACAGUAUGAGGUUGCACAACAAAAAGCUUCACAUGACCAAGAAUAUCUUUGUAACAUAGGGGACCUUGAGCUUCCUGAAGAAAGGCAACAGAAUCAACACAAAAUUGUUGAUUUGGAAGCUACGAUGAAAGGAAAUGGGCUCCCACAGAAUGUGGAUCCUCCAAGUGCGAAGAAAAGUAUUCCAUCUUCAGAAUGCAGUGGCUGCUCAAAUUCAGAAACAUUUAUGGAAAUCGAUACAGCUCAACAGUCCCUAGUUACUUUGCUUAAUUCAACAGGCAGGCAGAAUGCCAAUGUCAAGAACAUUGGUGCAUUGGAUCUCACUUUAGAUAAUCCCUUGAUGGAAGUAGAAACAUCAAAAUGUAACCCUUCAUCUGAAAUUUUGAAUGAUUCCAUUUCCACUCAGGAUUUACAGCCCCCAGAAACUAAUGUUGAAAUACCUGGAACAAAUAAAGAAUAUGGCCAUUACUCCUCUCCAAGUCUCUGUGGCAGUUGUCAGCCUUCUGUGGAGUCAGCAGAAGAAUCUUGCCCGUCUAUAACGGCAGCCUUGAAAGAACUUCAUGAACUUUUGGUUGUUAGCAGUAAACCAGCUUCAGAAAAUACAUCUGAAGAAGUAAUCUGUCAAUCAGAAACCAUAGCUGAGGGCCAAACCAGUAUUAAAGACCUUUCUGAAAGAUGGACCCAAAAUGAGCAUCUUACCCAGAAUGAACAGUGUCCACAAGUCUCCUUUCAUCAGGCCAUAUCUGUAUCAGUGGAGACAGAAAAAUUAACAGGUACUUCAUCUGACACUGGAAGAGAAGCUGUAGAAAAUGUAAACUUCAGGAGUCUAGGUGAUGGCCUGUCAACCGAUAAGGAAGGUGUCCCCAAAUCUAGGGAAUCCAUAAAUAAGAACCGUUCUGUCACUGUAACCUCAGCUAAAACAUCCAAUCAGUUACACUGCACCUUAGGUGUAGAAAUUUCACCCAAACUUUUAGCAGGUGAGGAGGAUGCACUCAAUCAGACUUCUGAGCAAACUAAGUCUUUGUCAUCCAAUUUCAUAUUGGUUAAAGACUUAGGUCAGGGCAUACAGAAUUCAGUAACAGACAGGCCUGAAACCAGAGAAAAUGUCUGUCCUGAUGCUUCGAGGCCAUUACUUGAAUAUGAACCACCUACCAGCCAUCCAUCAUCAAGUCCUGCCAUUCUUCCACCAUUGAUUUUUCCUGCCACAGAUAUUGACCGCAUUCUCCGUGCUGGCUUUACUUUGCAGGAAGCUCUUGGAGCUUUGCAUCGAGUUGGUGGGAAUGCAGACCUUGCACUUCUUGUUUUGCUCGCAAAAAACAUCGUAGUUCCUACAUGACUGUGGGAAAGUGGGCUAGACCGUUCUCCAUUCCCUUUAAACAAAAGAAAGCUCUCUCUAUAUACACGCACACAUACACACUCACCACAUAUACAGUAUAUAUAGAAACCUGCAAGCAGAAUGUUGAGCCAGAUUUUUUUUAAAGAUUUUUUUCGGCCAAAGUAAUUUAUGAUCUUUUGUCUGAUGAAUUUGUCUAUCCUACUUGUUAAAAUUUAGGCCUUUUUAAAUGUAUUGGCAGUAUGUGCAUACAGAAGCUUUUUAUUCUCAUUAAGAUGUAUCCUGGAAUAAAAUGGAUGGUUUUGUGUGUAGCA